GCCCAGAAAUUCUACCCAAGCUCCCUCAGCACCAUGUACCGAGCACUUCGGCUCCUCGCGCGCUCGCGUCCCCUCGUGCGGGCUCCAGCCGCAGCCUUAGCUUCGGCUCCCGGCUUGGGUGGCGCGGCCGUGCCCUCGUUUUGGCCUCCGAACGCGGCUCGAAUGGCAAGCCAAAAUUCCUUCCGGAUAGAAUAUGAUACCUUUGGUGAACUAAAGGUGCCAAAUGAUAAGUAUUAUGGCGCCCAGACCGUGAGAUCUACGAUGAACUUUAAGAUUGGAGGUGUGACAGAACGCAUGCCAACCCCAGUUAUUAAAGCUUUUGGCAUCUUGAAGCGAGCGGCCGCUGAAGUAAACCAGGAUUAUGGUCUUGAUCCAAAGAUUGCUAAUGCAAUAAUGAAGGCAGCAGAUGAGGUAGCUGAAGGUAAAUUAAAUGAUCAUUUUCCUCUCGUGGUAUGGCAGACUGGAUCAGGAACUCAGACAAAUAUGAAUGUAAAUGAAGUCAUUAGCAAUAGAGCAAUUGAAAUGUUAGGAGGUGAACUUGGCAGCAAGAUACCUGUGCAUCCCAACGAUCAUGUUAAUAAAAGCCAGAGCUCAAAUGAUACUUUUCCCACAGCAAUGCACAUUGCUGCUGCAAUAGAAGUUCAUGAAGUACUGUUACCAGGACUACAGAAGUUACAUGAUGCUCUUGAUGCAAAAUCCAAAGAGUUUGCACAGAUCAUCAAGAUUGGACGUACUCAUACUCAGGAUGCUGUUCCACUUACUCUUGGGCAGGAAUUUAGUGGUUAUGUUCAACAAGUAAAAUAUGCAAUGACAAGAAUAAAAGCUGCCAUGCCAAGAAUCUAUGAGCUCGCAGCUGGAGGCACUGCUGUUGGUACAGGUUUAAAUACUAGAAUUGGCUUUGCAGAAAAGGUUGCUGCAAAAGUGGCUGCACUUACAGGCUUGCCUUUUGUCACUGCUCCGAAUAAAUUUGAAGCUCUGGCUGCUCAUGACGCUCUGGUUGAGCUCAGUGGAGCCAUGAACACUACUGCCUGCAGUCUGAUGAAGAUAGCAAAUGAUAUUCGAUUUUUGGGUUCUGGUCCUCGGUCAGGUCUGGGAGAAUUGAUCUUGCCUGAAAAUGAACCAGGAAGCAGUAUCAUGCCAGGCAAGGUGAACCCUACUCAGUGUGAAGCAAUGACCAUGGUUGCAGCCCAAGUCAUGGGGAACCAUGUUGCUGUCACUGUCGGAGGCAGCAAUGGACAUUUUGAGUUGAAUGUUUUCAAGCCAAUGAUGAUUAAAAAUGUGUUACACUCAGCCAGGCUGCUGGGGGAUGCUUCAGUUUCCUUUACAGAAAACUGCGUGGUGGGAAUCCAGGCCAAUACAGAAAGGAUCAACAAGCUGAUGAAUGAGUCUCUAAUGUUGGUGACAGCUCUCAAUCCUCAUAUAGGGUAUGACAAGGCAGCAAAGAUUGCUAAGACAGCACACAAAAAUGGAUCAACCUUAAAGGAAACUGCUAUCGAACUUGGCUAUCUCACAGCAGAGCAGUUUGACGAAUGGGUAAAACCUAAGGACAUGCUGGGUCCAAAGUGAUUUACAUAAAUUUAUAAUGAAAAUAAACAUGUAUAAAAUUUAAAAAAACAGACUCCCAUUUCUUAAAAACGGAUAAGUUUGAAAGGAAACUGCUAUUGAACUUAAGCAUCUCUAGCAGAGCAAUUUGAUCAGUAUAUAAAACCCUAGGAUGUGCUAGGUCUAAGAUGGAUUAAACAAGUAUAAAAUAAAAUACAUUUAUAAAAUAAAAAGGAAAACAGACUUAAA